GACACCCUAGAUCCCAAGAUCUCCAAGGAUUUGGUGGCAUACCCACUCCAGCACACAGAAGCAUGAGGUUCAUGACUCUCCUCUUCCUGACAGCUCUGGCAGGAGCCCUGGUCUGUGCCUAUGAUCCAGAGGCCGCCUCUGCCCCAGGAUCGGGGAACCCUUGCCAUGAAGCAUCAGCAGCUCAAAAGGAAAAUGCAGGUGAAGACCCAGGGUUAGCCAGACAGGCACCAAAGCCAAGGAAGCAGAGAUCCAGCCUUCUGGAAAAAGGCCUAGACGGAGCAAAAAAAGCUGUGGGGGGACUCGGAAAACUAGGAAAAGAUGCAGUCGAAGAUCUAGAAAGCGUGGGUAAAGGUGGGGAAGAGAGGUUGGUCUUUGGGGCUCCUGUGAAUCUAACCUCCAUCCCUCUGACUUCUGUGAGCCGUCCAUGACGUUAAAGACGUCCUUGACUCAGUACUAUAGCUGUAAGGAGAAGCUGAGAAAUGAUACCCAGGAGCAGCAGGCUUUACGUCUUCAGCCUAAAACCUAAAAAAAAAAAAAAAAAAAAAAAUUUAAAACAGCUAUUAAACUGAAAGCAUCUGUAAUA